GGUCGCGCGUACUCCUCCUCCCAAGUAGGGAGCGGGCGCAUGAUGGCGGCCGCGGCGGCAGCGGCUGCGGGGAGCUCCAGCAGCGGCGGCGGCGGCGGCGGCAGCGGCAGCAGCAGCAGCAGCAGCGACACGUCCAGCACCGGCGAGGAGGAGAGGAUGCGGCGCCUCUUCCAGACGUGCGACGGCGACGGGGACGGAUACAUCAGCAGAAAUGACUUGCUAAUGGUCUGUCGCCAGCUGAAUAUGGAAGAGUCUGUGGCUGAGAUCAUGAACCAGUUGGGAGCAGAUGAAAAUGGGAAGAUUUCCUUUCAGGAUUUCACAAGAUGCCGCAUGCAGCUUGUUCGAGAAAUUAGGAAGGAGGAAGUAGAUCUUUCUGCAAAGUCAGACAACUCCUGUACAAAGAAGCUGAGGGAUAGAAUUGCUUCCUGGCCCACGAGCAGUGACAACAGUUUGGGUGCCUUAUCAGCAGCCAGGGAGAGCUGGGAAUACGACUCUGGUGCCAGGGACCUCCAGAGCCCGGAUGUGCAGAGCCAGUCAGCCCUCCAGAAGCUGCUCGAGUAUGGCGGAAGCUCUUUGCAUCAGCAGGCUGCUCUCCACAAACUGCUCACACAGUCCCCGCACAUUGGCAACUCUGUAGGAGGAAGCUAUCUAGAGCUGGCCAACACACUCCAUUCAGCAGCCCUGGCAUCACUAAAGGGAGAUAUAGUGGAACUUAAUAAACGUCUCCAGCAAACAGAGAGGGAACGGGACCUUCUGGAAAAGAAAUUGGCCAAGGCACAGUGCGAGCAGUCCCACCUCAUGAGAGAGCAUGAGGAUGUCCAGGAGCGAACGACACUUCGCUAUGAGGAACGCAUCACAGAGCUCCACAGCGUCAUUGCGGAGCUCAACAAGAAGAUAGACCGUCUGCAAGGCACCACCAUCAGGGAGGAAGAUGAGUACUCAGAACUGCGAUCAGAACUCAGCCAGAGCCAACACGAGGUCAACGAGGACUCUCGAAGCAUGGACCAAGACCAGACCUCUGUCUCUAUCCCCGAAAACCAGUCUACCAUGGUUACUGCUGACAUGGACAACUGCAGUGACCUGAACUCAGAACUGCAGAGGGUGCUGACAGGGCUGGAGAAUGUUGUCUGCGGCAGGAAGAAGAGCAGCUGCAGCCUCUCCGUGGCCGAGGUGGACAAGCACAUUGAGCAGCUCACCACAGCCAGCGAGCACUGUGACCUGGCUAUUAAGACAGUCGAGGAGAUUGAGGGGGUGCUUGGCCGGGACCUGUAUCCCAACCUGGCUGAAGAGAGGUCUCGGUGGGAGAAGGAGCUGGCUGGGCUGAGGGAAGAGAAUGAGAGCCUGACUGCCAUGCUGUGCAGCAAAGAGGAAGAACUGAACCGGACUAAGGCCACCAUGAAUGCCAUCCGGGAAGAGCGGGACCGGCUCCGGAGGAGGGUCAGAGAGCUUCAAACUCGACUACAGAGCGUGCAGGCCACAGGUCCCUCCAGCCCUGGCCGCCUCACUUCCACCAACCGCCCGAUUAACCCCAGCACUGGGGAGCUGAGCACAAGCAGCAGCAGCAAUGACAUUCCCAUCGCCAAGAUUGCUGAGAGGGUGAAGCUAUCAAAGACAAGGUCCGAAUCGUCAUCAUCUGAUCGGCCAGUCCUGGGCUCAGAAAUCAGUAGCAUAGGGGUAUCCAGCAGUGUGGCUGAACACCUGGCCCACUCACUUCAGGACUGCUCCAAUAUCCAAGAGAUUUUCCAAACACUCUACUCACACGGAUCUGCCAUCUCAGAAAGCAAGAUUAGAGAGUUUGAGGUGGAAACAGAACGGCUGAAUAGCCGGAUUGAGCACCUCAAAUCCCAAAAUGACCUCCUGACCAUAACCUUGGAGGAAUGUAAAAGCAAUGCCGAGAGGAUGAGCAUGCUGGUGGGAAAAUACGAAUCCAAUGCCACAGCGCUGAGGCUGGCCUUGCAGUACAGCGAGCAGUGCAUCGAAGCCUACGAACUCCUCCUGGCGCUGGCAGAGAGUGAGCAGAGCCUCAUCCUGGGGCAGUUCCGAGCGGCGGGCGUGGGGUCCUCCCCUGGAGACCAGUCGGGGGAUGAAAACAUCACUCAGAUGCUCAAGCGAGCUCAUGACUGCCGGAAGACAGCUGAGAACGCUGCCAAGGCCCUGCUCAUGAAGCUGGACGGCAGCUGUGGGGGAGCCUUUGCCGUGGCCGGCUGCAGCGUGCAGCCCUGGGAGAGCCUUUCCUCCAACAGCCACACCAGCACAACCAGCUCCACAGCCAGUAGUUGCGACACCGAGUUCACUAAAGAAGACGAGCAGAGGCUGAAGGAUUAUAUCCAGCAGCUCAAGAAUGACAGGGCUGCGGUCAAGCUGACCAUGCUGGAGCUGGAAAGCAUCCACAUCGAUCCUCUCAGCUAUGACGUCAAGCCUCGGGGAGACAGCCAGAGGCUGGAUCUGGAAAACGCAGUGCUUAUGCAGGAGCUCAUGGCCAUGAAGGAGGAGAUGGCCGAGUUGAAGGCCCAGCUCUACCUACUGGAGAAAGAGAAGAAGGCCCUGGAGCUGAAGCUGAGCACGCGGGAGGCCCAGGAGCAGGCCUACCUGGUGCACAUUGAGCACCUGAAGUCCGAGGUGGAGGAGCAGAAGGAGCAGCGGAUGCGAUCCCUCAGCUCCACCAGCAGCGGCAGCAAAGACAAACCUGGCAAGGAGUGUGCUGAUGCUGCCUCCCCAGCUCUGUCCCUAGCCGAACUCAGGACAACGUGCAGCGAGAAUGAGCUGGCUGCGGAGUUCACCAACGCCAUUCGUCGAGAAAAGAAGUUGAAGGCCAGAGUUCAAGAGCUGGUGAGUGCCUUGGAGAGACUCACCAAGAGCAGUGAAAUCCGACAUCAGCAAUCUGCAGAGUUCGUGAAUGAUCUAAAGCGGGCCAACAGCAACCUGGUGGCUGCCUAUGAGAAAGCAAAGAAAAAGCAUCAAAACAAACUGAAGAAGUUAGAGUCGCAGAUGAUGGCCAUGGUGGAGAGACAUGAGACCCAAGUGAGGAUGCUCAAGCAAAGAAUAGCUCUGCUAGAGGAGGAGAACUCCAGGCCACACACCAAUGAAACUUCGCUUUAAUCAGCACUCACGCACCGGAGUUCUGCCCAUGGGAAGUAAACUGCAGCAGGCCACUGGGGACAGAAGGGCCCAUGUACUUGUUGGGAGGAGGAGGAAAGGGAAGGCUGGCAGGUAGGUCGGCACUUGGACAAUGGAGUGCCCCAACUCAACCCUUGGGGCGACUGGCCAUGGUGACAUUGUGGACUGUAUCCAGAGGUGCCCGCUCUUCCCUCCUGGGCCCACAACAGCGUGUAAACACAUGUUCUGUGCCUGCUCAGCAGAGCCUCGUUUCUGCUUUCAGCACUCACUCUCCCCCUCCUCUUCUGGUCUGGCGGCUGUGCAUCAGUGGGAUCCCAGACAUUUGUUUCUGUAAGAUUUUCCAUUGUAUCCUCUUUUUGGUAGAUGCUGGGCUCAUCUUCUAGAAUCUCGUUUCUCCUCUUUCCUCCUGCUUCAUGGGAAAACAGACCUGUGUGUGCCUCCAGCAUUUAAAAGGACUGCUGAUUUGUUUACUACAGCAAGGCUUUGGUUUCCAAGUCCCGGGUCUCAACUUUAAGAUAGAGGCGGCCAUAAGAGGUGAUCUCUGGGAGUUAUAGGUCAUGGGAAGAGCGUAGACAGGUGUUACUUACAGUCCCAGAUACACUAAAGUUACAAACAGACCACCACCAGGACUGUGCCUGAACAAUUUUGUAUUGAGAGAAUAAAAACUUCCUUCAAUCUUCAUUUUGGAGGCAGGGCUGGGAAGGGAGCGCUCUCUUGAUUCUGGGAUUUCUCCCUCUCAGUGGAGCCUUAUUAAUAUCCAAGACUUAGAGCUGGGAAUCUUUUUGAUACCUGUAGUGGAACUAAAAUUCUGUCAGGGGUUUCUUCAAGAGCUGAGAAACAUUAUUAGCACUUCCCGCCCCAGGGCACUACAUAAUUGCUGUUCUGCUGAAUCAAAUCUCUUCCACAUGGGUGCAUUUGUAGCUCUGGACCUGUCUCUACCUAAGGACAAGACACUGAGGAGAUACUGAACAUUUUGCAAAACUUAUCACGCCUACUUAAGAGUGCUGUGUAACCCCCAGUUCAAGACUUAGCUCCUGUUGUCAUGACGGGGACAGAGUGAGGGAAUGGUAGUUAAGGCUUCUUUUUUGCCCCCAGAUACAUGGUGAUGGUUAGCAUAUGGUGCUUAAAAGGUUAAAUUUCAAGCAAAAUGCUUACAGGGCUAGGCAGUACCAAAGUAACUGAAUUAUUUCAGGAAGGUCUUCAAUCUUAAAACAAAUUCAUUAUUCUUUUUCAGUUUUACCUCUUCUCUCUCAGUUCUACACUGAUACACUUGAAGGACCAUUUACUGUUUUUUUCUGUAGCACCAGAGAAUCCAUCCAAAGUUCCCUAUGAAAAAUGUGUUCCAUUGCCAUAGCUGACUACAAAUUAAAGUUGAGGAGGUUUCUGCAUAGAGUCUUUAUGUCCAUAAGCUACGGGUAGGUCUAUUUUCAGAGCAUGAUACAAAUUCCACAGCCUUCUGUUCGCUGGAGGAUACUCCAGCCACCAGUUCGGAGGGCAGACAGCUGUAUCCUAAAAGCAACCACUGAGAGGCCAGCAGUGAGGCUGCCCAUCUCCAAAACGAAACAACAGAUCAACUGGUAUCAGUCUAGAAGGACCAGCUUUGGGGUGCUUUGAUCACUAUGAAAAUGUUCACUGGUUUCUGUCAAUCAUUUGGUCAAAGUUAGUUCCUGUGAUUUUUUUUUUUUUUUUUUGAGAUGGAGUUUUGCUCGUCACCAGGCUGAAGUGCAGUGGCGUGAUCUUGGCUCACUGCAACCUCUGCCUCCUGAGUAGCUGGAAUUACAGGUGCCCGCCACCAUACCCAGCUAGUUUUUUUGUAUUUUUAGUAGAGACAGGGUUUCACCAUGUUGGCCAGGCUGGUCUCGAACUCCUGACCACUGAUCCACCCACCUCGGCCUCCCAAAGUGCUGGGAUUACAGGCAUGAGCCAAUGUGCCUGGCCAUUCCUGUGAUUUUUUAGAAUUUUUCACUUUUCAUAUAAAGUUGCAUUUUAUCAUGAGGAAAAUGUUUUGGCUGAAAAACAUAUGCCCCAAAAAAAAAAAAAUCAGUUUUCACUAUUUUUCCAGCUUGCCUAGGGAAACGUCCUCCCCUGAGCAAAGUGGGAUGUGCAUGGCUCUUUUUUGUGAUUAAGCAGGCAUCAAAUGGGCAGUUUUCAUUUUCACUGACACAGAAACAUGUGGCUGAAGCAGGAAUAAAAUCCUGCCUACUGACUUCUGUCUCCAUUCUUGCUCCAGGUAAAAUCAGAGAACCUCCCCUUCUCUGAGAAUUCCCCCAGGCAGAGGCGGCUCCAGCUCCUGUUAAGGGCCCCAGUUUUACUCAUGCUACCUGACCUUAGUUUUAGUACUUUCAAAUGUGAUUUGGGUAAAAACUAUUUUGCAGGCAAAAGUGUUAAUUUUUUAUAAAUAUGUAUAAUAAAAAAGCUAUAAAAGUUUUUCCUUUUCUUGUAUUUUUCAAAUACUCCCCAAGACACAAUCCUUGAAGGUGAACUAGGUGGCACUUGAUUAUGCUAAUUGUGGGAGCUACUGAACUAAACUAUACUGAUUAAAUUAAAUGCUUGCAGGUUCCUGGGUAAUUUUCCUUUGUGAAUAACCUGGCGCUACCUGAAUUUUUCUCUAACAAACAUCUCCAAUGAGGGUAAACAAUGAUCUUGAUUCUAAUUUAUAUGAGGUUAAAAACCUUCAGAUUUCGUAUUUUGAAUUGUUCUCCCUAGUUUCCUCAGUGGUUACCCCCUUUUAGUCAGUAACCAUCUCUGUUCAGAAUUCAGUCUUUGGCUUUUGAAGAAAUGGGCACAGAGCCAAAGGACCCAUUUCACAGUUCCCUUGGAAUAUAUUUCCCAUUGUUGGACUGAGGCAAACAAAACCAACUGUGCAAAUCACAAGCAAAAGAGACUUCUGUCCGUAGUUGCGAGUGCCAUCAGUGUGAGCUUACCAGCUACAAAAAUCUGUCAUGGACUGGGGAACAGUAUGAUUCCUUAUUGAAACUUUCAUCCUCAUCGGCUGGCUUGUCAGCGUUCUGAAGUUAAUAUCCAUGCUGCCUGAAACAAAUGUUAUGUUUAACUAGCACUUAACUUUUAAAAUUGCUUAAUUCUCCUUUCAGAUGCAUGCACUAAGUCUUCUCUGAGCCUGCAGCAAUAUUUUAGAGGGACCUCUUCUAAGUCAGAGCCUUGACAUUCUACUCCAAAAGGAAGUCCAAAUUAGAGCCCAUAGGCUUUUUCUUAAAAGCUGUUAAGGAGUAGUAAAGAAAGUUACCACUCUAAGGAAAACAUGAAACUAUCUGAAAGUCUUCUGGUUCCUAACUGGAUACAGAUUAGAUUAUUUUAAAUGAGAAAAAAGUGCACCGUAGUUACCCGAUCAAGAUUGGACUGCCUGUGUCCCUGGCAUGAAUUAAAGAACCUCCAUAGUUGCUUGUUCCCUUCUGAAGGUGUUUCCUAUGGCCCACGAGAAUUAUAAAGCAAUCACUUUUUAAGUCUAUCAGUCAACCUUAAUAGCUCUCAAGAGUUUCGAUUAUCAAGCUUUAAAGUGAUAACAUAUCAAGAUGACUAUUAAAAAAUAAACAUCUCUGAAAGUGUCCUUUCCUCCAUAAGGCUUUAAACAAUUUGCAAAUUCUUAAUUGGGAGUAUGUCCCAAUCAUUCUAUUAAACUAUUUACAGCUCUACCUACUUCUAGAUUCAGCAAACAGAGCUACUAGUUAGAGUAUUUUGAGAGCCAAAAUAGUAAGAGACUUCUGUAAUGGUUGAGAUUUCUGCACUGACCUUAAUUAGGGUACCGCCAUAGGGCUACCAAAGUUUUUAGUGAGGGCUGGGGAGGUGGAGCAUAAGUAACAUUUUUUUUCUGCAGAAGGUGAUGGCUUUGUAGAACACUAUAAAAUUUUUCAGGAAAACAUACAGCAAAUUUUCUUAUCCAGUGGGAACAGCCUAUUUGACAAGGAAUGAUAUACAAGUUUGAUUCACCUUUGAGCACUCUUAUAGAGUUUACAGAAGAGGCGUAACUGGUUACAAAACAAAAGUUACGCCUUCACUAUCCAGUUCUUAAAGUUUAUCCACAUCCUACAAAUCUUAUGUUCAUGUAGGUCAGGUUAAAGUAAGCUCCAAACUUGUGGCCUUCAGAAGCAUCUCCUGUUUAACACACCUGAAAUUACUCUAACUUAAUACAUUUGUAUUCUCUAAGAAAUAAUGCUGACUGCUGUCACCACAGCAUCACUGAUCUCUCAGUGGCUGUUAAAAUAUAAACAAGUGGAAAAAAAGUAUACAAGUUGAUAGCAGCUGUUCAUGUAUUCUUGUUUUGCUAAUACCUGUGUAGAGAAAGACAGUUUCACAUGCAGAUCACCAUACAUUUUUGCUUAAAGGUUACACUGGGUAAACUGUUUGUUUAUCACAUUACAUCUGGGUGAGAUUUUGCAUGUGACCAAGAGGAAGAAAUCAUUCAGUCCCGGAAAUAGCAACUGCUAUGUAAAACCACAUCCUUGACUAGUACUUCAUCUUUCCACAGUCAUCCAUCUGCUAAUCAGGUGAAAUAUCAGCUCAGCAGAACAAAGCAAGUUAUACACAAAUUUCCCCCACAUUCACACUGAUGCCGUACUUAGUAAUUCUGGUUCUACCAUUCCCUUUUGCACUUUUUGCAAGUCAAAUUCAUGUGGAAAAAUGUUCUGUUUGUAGAACUCAUAGUAUUCACUUAUAGUGCUCAUGUCAGGAAUGGCAAGUGAGUAAGAGCCCCUGAUAAUCUGCUUUUGUUAGAACGUAAUGCAAAGAUAAUAAAACAUGUCCACUUCUUUUCUAGUUCUAAUCAGUUUUUAGACAUCAAGAUUUAUUUACUUUGCAUGAGAUUUGUUUCCUAUUAUUUGAAUAUGUGCUAUACACUUGAAUUAGAAAAACCUGCUUGAAUGUAUUGUCAGUUAUUAAAGCACAUGUGACUAAGUUUGCAUUUGUCAGUAUUGUUCUACUGUUUGUACUGAAAGUCUCAUUUUAAAAUUGCUACUUAACACUGUACUAUACCUUGUAAUUUUUUAGAUUCUCCACUUGUAUUCUUUAAAUGUUUCCAGAUGCCUUUAGUUUUAGCUGCUGUAAAAUAGCUACUUUGCGUUAUUUGAUAUAGAAUUGUUUUUUAAAAACUCCAUUUAUUUAUACAGAGACAUUUAUAAUAUUUUACAAACAUUCUUAUAUUCUGAAUAAAUAUUUCUAAUUCCA